AGUUCAGCGGCCCCGAGAGUCCGGGGAGGGAGGUUUAUUCUCCGCCUGCACGAGACUGUGAAAUCCGCAACCAUGAGCAGGAGAGGCGGCCCUGGUGGGGAAGAGGCCACCAACAUCUGGACGGCAGCCCUGCUCAGGCAUUCGGCAGGUCCAGCAGAGGUACACCUCCUGCAGCGGGUUCCAAGUGCACCUCCAGCCUGAUGGGCCUGACCAAGGAGGCUUCCAGGAGCACAGAAGGGGCUGCAACCCAGGUACCCAGAGAGUGAGCAGCUCCACGCGGGACUGUGCACGGUGGCCGACACCCGCAGGGACGCCCGCCGGACGAGCACGCGGAGGGCCCUCGCCUCCACGGAUGCACCAUGCCGGUGUGAGGAGCAUCUGUUCUUCCCACUCUCUGCAGUUAACAAACCCAACCCAAACCACCACAGGUGCUCCUCCUGGGGAGUUUCCUGUCUGACAAAUGCCAGGCUCACUUCAAGGAGAAUCACGCUUCUUUCUAAAGAUGGAUUCACCAUUUAAAACAGAGCUCUGGGAGCCUUUCGGCAAAUCUUGAAAGCUGCACGGUGCAGAGACAUGGAUGUGACUUCCCAAGCCCGGGGCGUGGGCCUGGAGAUGUACCCAGGCACCGCGCAGCCUGCGGCCCCCAACACCACCUCCCCCGAGCUCAACCUGUCCCACCCGCUCCUGGGCACCGCCCUGGCCAAUGGGACAGGUGAGCUCUCGGAGCACCAGCAGUACGUGAUCGGCCUGUUCCUCUCGUGCCUCUACACCAUCUUCCUCUUCCCCAUCGGCUUUGUGGGCAACAUCCUGAUCCUGGUGGUGAACAUCAGCUUCCGCGAGAAGAUGACCAUCCCCGACCUGUACUUCAUCAACCUGGCGGUGGCGGACCUCAUCCUGGUGGCCGACUCCCUCAUUGAGGUGUUCAACCUGCACGAGCGGUACUACGACAUCGCCGUCCUGUGCACCUUCAUGUCGCUCUUCCUGCAGGUCAACAUGUACAGCAGCGUCUUCUUCCUCACCUGGAUGAGCUUCGACCGCUACAUCGCCCUGGCCAGGGCCAUGCGCUGCAGCCUGUUCCGCACCAAGCACCACGCCCGGCUGAGCUGUGGCCUCAUCUGGAUGGCAUCCGUGUCAGCCACGCUGGUGCCCUUCACCGCCGUGCACCUGCAGCACACCGACGAGGCCUGCUUCUGUUUCGCGGAUGUCCGGGAGGUGCAGUGGCUCGAGGUCACGCUGGGCUUCAUCGUGCCCUUCGCCAUCAUCGGCCUGUGCUACUCCCUCAUUGUCCGGGUGCUGGUCAGGGCGCACCGGCACCGUGGGCUGCGGCCCCGGCGGCAGAAGGCGCUCCGCAUGAUCCUCGCGGUGGUGCUGGUCUUCUUCGUCUGCUGGCUGCCGGAGAACGUCUUCAUCAGCGUGCACCUCCUGCAGCGGACGCAGCCUGGGGCCGCUCCCUGCAAGCAGUCUUUCCGCCAUGCCCACCCCCUCACGGGCCACAUUGUCAACCUCGCCGCCUUCUCCAACAGCUGCCUAAACCCCCUCAUCUACAGCUUUCUCGGGGAGACCUUCAGGGACAAGCUGAGGCUGUACAUUGAGCAGAAAACAAAUUUGCCGGCCCUGAACCGCUUCUGUCACGCUGCCCUGAAGGCCGUCAUUCCAGACAGCACCGAGCAGUCGGAUGUGAGGUUCAGCAGUGCCGUGUAGACAGCCUUGGCCGCAUAGGCCCAGCCAGGGUGUGACUCGGGAGCUGCACACACCUGGGUGGACACAAGGCACGGCCACGUCAUGUCUCUAAACUGCGGUCAGAUGUGGCUUCUGGCUCCUCGGGGCCUCGCGAGGGUCACGCUUGCCUGGUCACCCUGGGGCUGCUUAGGAAACCUCACGACUGGUCACCUUGCACUCCUCACACAGAAUUGCUACAAUCCCAAAGCGCUCGCCCCGCAGGGUCCAAAGGCCAGCGGUGACCAGCCUGUCACCCAGCUCCUCCCCGCCAACCCUGCCUGCCGCUGCACCUGCCUGCCGCUGCAGGAAACAUUUCUGACACCGUCGACCAGGAAAGCCACACGGAGAGGCCACUGUGGGUGAAGCGCCUCAGUUACACAGGAACCCUAAAGCAAAUCUGCCACCGUGGGGGAACUGACGCUGGAGAUGCAAGGUGCUGGUGGGUCUGAGCUGGACGUCGCGGUGUGUCCUCUGUGCCCACGGUCUGAGCUAGCUAGCGCACCGCCGAGUUAAAGAGGAGAAGGAAAACAUGCUGCUCUGGUGCACGCCUGAGCGUCCUCCAUCUUCCAGGAUGGCAGCAAUGGCGCUGUGCGGCCUCACCAGGCCCACGAGGAGCAGCAGCGCUCGGCCCGGAGCAGCAGGAAGGCCCCUCUGUGGAGCGCCCGCCGUCUGCUCCGGGGUGGUUCAGUCACUGCUUGUUGACAUCAACAUGGCAAUUGCACUCAUGUGGACUGGGACCGUGCGAGCUGCCGUGUGGGUUAGUCGGGUGCCAGGACAAUGAAAUACUCCAGCACCUGUGGCUGACGAAUUUGUUUCUACAGAAAUAACAGCUGGGGACAACUGCGGUGAUGAUGUAAAAACCUUCCCAUAAAAUGUAAGAAAAGCUGAUGAGGCUGGUGACGUUCAGCCUUUGUCAAUAAACCUGUCAUGUGCGGA